GUUCCCCAGCUCUCCCGGGACGAAGCGGGCCCGCCAGCGAGUCGCAGUCCCAGGAGCCGAGCUCCAGCACUAGAGCCAGCUGCGAGCGGAGGGCACCAACUCCGCAGAACUGGCUUUUCAAUGGGACACCUGUGGCUCCUGGGUAUUUGGGGCCUCUGUGGGCUGCUCCUGUGUGCCGCGGAUCCCAGCACAGAUGGCUCUCAAAUAAUCCCCAAAGUCACAGAAAUAAUACCUAAAUAUGGCAGUAUAAAUGGAGCAACAAGGCUGACUAUAAGAGGGGAAGGUUUUUCUCAAGCAAACCAGUUUAACUAUGGAGUUGAUAACGCUGAGUUGGGAAACAGUGUGCAAUUAAUUUCUUCUUUCCAGUCAAUUACUUGUGAUGUAGAAAAAGAUGCAAGUCAUUCAACUCAAAUUACAUGCUAUACUAGAGCAAUGCCGGAAGAUUCCUACACUGUUAGAGUCAGUGUGGACGGGGUUCCUGUUACGGAAAAUAACACCUGCAAAGGUCACAUCAACAGCUGGGAAUGUACCUUCAACGCAAAAAGUUUUAGAACCCCAACAAUAAGAAGCAUCACACCUUUAUCUGGAACUCCAGGUACACUAAUAACAAUCCAAGGCAGAAUCUUCACUGAUGUCUAUGGAAGUAAUAUUGCACUAAGCUCAAAUGGGAAAAAUGUUAGGAUUUUGAGAGUUUACAUUGGAGGAAUGCCCUGUGAGCUUCUCAUACCACAAUCUGAUAAUUUAUAUGGUCUAAAACUGGAUCAUCCAAAUGGAGAUAUGGGUUCUAUGGUUUGUAAGACGACUGGAACUUUUAUUGGUCAUCACAAUGUCAGCUUCAUCUUAGAUAAUGAUUAUGGAAGGAGUUUUCCACAGAAAAUGGCAUAUUUUGUUUCUUCUCUCAAUAAAAUUGCAAUGUUUCAAACAUAUGCAGAGGUCACCAUGAUUUUCCCUUCACAAGGAAGCAUUCGAGGUGGCACCACGCUGACAAUAAGUGGGCGUUUCUUUGAUCAGACAGAUUUCCCCGUCAGAGUUCUAGUUGGAGGUGAACCUUGUGAUAUUUUGAAUGUCACAGAAAAUAGUAUAUGUUGCAAGACACCCCCCAAACCUCAUAUUCUCAAAACUGUAUAUCCAGGAGGGAGAGGCCUGAAGCUUGAGGUGUGGAAUAAUAGCCGUCCAAUACGUUUGGAAGAGAUACUGGAAUACAAUGAAAAAACGCCUGGGUACAUGGGUGCCAGUUGGGUAGAUUCAGCUUCCUAUAUUUGGCUCAUGGAACAAGACACAUUUGUUGCACGCUUUAGUGGAUUUUUGGUGGCUCCAGAUUCUGAUGUUUAUAGAUUCUACAUCAAGGGUGAUGACCGUUAUGCUAUUUAUUUUAGCCAGACUGGACUUCCAGAAGAUAAGGUGAGGAUUGCAUAUCAUUCUGCUAAUGCCAACAGUUAUUUUUCCAGUCCAACACAAAGAUCAGAUGAUAUUCAUCUGCAGAAAGGAAAAGAAUACUAUAUUGAAAUCUUGCUGCAGGAGUACAGAUUAAGUGCAUUUGUUGAUGUUGGACUGUACCAGUAUCGAAAUGUUUAUACUGAACAACAAACAGGAGAUGCAGUGAAUGAAGAACAAGUUAUCAAAUCCCAGUCGACAAUCCUCCAGGAAGUACAGGUUAUAACAUUGGAAAACUGGGAAACAACUAAUGCAAUUAAUGAGGUUCAGAAGAUCAAGGUAACCAGCCCAUGUGUGGAAGCUAAUUCAUGUUCACUUUACCAAUAUAGAUUAAUCUAUAAUAUGGAAAAAACUGUCUUCCUACCUGCUGAUGCUUCUGAAUUCAUACUGCAAUCAGCCUUGAAUGACCUCUGGUCUAUAAAACCGGACACAGUUCAAGUAAUAAGAACACAAAAUCCCCAGAGCUAUGUCUACAUGGUAACAUUCAUAUCAACUAGAGGAGACUUUGAUCUGCUUGGUUAUGAAGUAGUUGAAGGGAAUAAUGUCACACUGGAUAUUACAGAACAAACCAAAGGAAAACCCAACUUGGAGACAUUCACACUGAAUUGGGAUGGGAUCGCUUCUAAGCCACUCACUCUAUGGUCAUCAGAAGCUGAAUUUCAGGGAGCAGUGGAAGAAAUGGUUAGCACUAAGUGUCCACCACAAAUUGCAAAUUUUGAAGAAGGAUUUGUUGUGAAAUAUUUCAGAGACUAUGAAACUGAUUUUAAUCUGGAACAUAUUAACAGAGGGCAGAAGACAGCUGAAACCGAUGCUUACUGUGGUCGUUAUUCCCUGAAAAACCCAGCUGUUCUUUUUGACUCAGCAGAUGUUAAACCAAACAGACGACCAUAUGGAGAUAUUUUAUUGUUUCCUUAUAAUCAGUUAUGUUUAGCAUACAAAGGAUUCCUGGCAAAUUAUAUUGGUCUAAAAUUUCAGUACCAAGACAAUAGCAAGAUUACUAGAAGCACUGAUACACAGUUUACAUACAACUUUGCUUAUGGAAACAACUGGACUUACACUUGCAUAGACCUUCUGGAUCUCGUAAGAACGAAAUACACUGGGACAAAUGUUUCUCUUCAGAGGAUUAGCUUACAUAAAGCAUCAGAAUCACAGUCCUUCUAUGUGGAUGUAGUGUACAUUGGACACACAUCUACAAUCUCAACAUUGGAUGAAAUGCCCAAGAGAAGACUUCCUGCAUUAGCAAAUAAAGGAAUAUUCUUAGAGCACUUUCAGGUGAAUCAGACCAAAACAAAUGGGCCAACUAUGACAAACCAAUAUUCUGUUACCAUGACUUCAUACAAUUGCAGUUACAAUAUACCCAUGAUGGCUGUGAGCUUUGGGCAGAUAAUCACACAUGAGACAGAGAACGAGUUUGUCUACAGAGGAAAUAAUUGGCCAGGCGAGUCAAAAAUUCAUAUUCAAAGAAUUCAAGCUGCAUCUCCACCUCUAAGUGGCAGCUUUGACAUUCAAGCUUAUGGACAUAUUCUUAAAGGCCUCCCCGCUGCUGUGUCAGCUGCAGAUCUGCAGUUUGCACUCCAGAGUCUGGAGGGAAUGGGAAGAAUCUCAGUUACACGAGAGGGAACCUGUGCUGGCUACGCGUGGAACAUCAAAUGGAGAAGCACCUGCGGAAAGCAGAAUCUUCUACAGAUUAAUGAUUCCAACAUUAUUGGAGAAAAGGCUAAUAUGACAGUUACAAGGAUAAAGGAAGGUGGCUUAUUCAGACAACAUGUACUUGGAGACCUACUUCGUACACCCAGUCAACAGCCACAGGUUGAAGUCUAUGUCAAUGGAAUUCCAGCUAAAUGUUCAGGUGACUGUGGAUUUACAUGGGAUUCCAACAUUACUCCCCUAGUCUUGGCGAUAAGCCCUUCUCAAGGGUCCUAUGAAGAAGGCACAAUUCUAACCAUAGUGGGUUCUGGAUUUUCUCCUAGUUCAGCUGUAACAGUCUCAGUUGGACCAGUAGGUUGUUCUCUUCUUUCUGUGGAUGAAAAAGAGCUCAAGUGCCAGAUUCUGAAUGGAAGUGCUGGACAUGCCCCCGUUGCUGUGUCCAUGGCUGAUGUUGGACUAGCACAGAAUGUAGGGGGUGAAGAGUUCUACUUUGUUUAUCAGAGUCAGAUCUCACAUAUCUGGCCUGAUUCUGGAAGCAUAGCAGGUGGUACUCUACUGACUUUAUCUGGAUUUGGCUUUAAUGAAAAUUCAAAGGUAUUAGUUGGAAAUGAAACCUGCAAUGUGAUUGAAGGGGAUUUGAAUAGGAUAACCUGCAGGACACCAAAAAAAACUGAGGGUACAGUUGAUAUUUCAGUUACUACCAAUGGAUUUCAAGCCACAGCAAGGGAUGCUUUUAGUUAUAAUUGUUUACAGACACCAAUUAUAACUGAUUUUAGUCCAAAAGUACGAACAAUACUAGGAGAAGUUAAUUUAACAAUUAAGGGCUAUAAUUUUGGAAAUGAACUCACACAAAACAUGGCGGUGUAUGUUGGAGGAAAAACCUGCCAGAUUCUUCACUGGAACUUCACAGAUAUUAGAUGCCUUUUGCCCAAGUUGUCUCCUGGAAAACAUGAUAUCUAUGUAGAAGUCAGAAACUGGGGUUUUGCAUCAACAAGAGACAAAUUAAAUUCUUCAAUACAGUAUGUUUUAGAAGUGACCAGCAUGUUUCCACAAAGAGGCUCCUUGUUUGGUGGAACUGAAAUCACCAUAAGGGGUUUUGGAUUCAGCACAAUACCAGCUGAGAAUACCGUGCUGUUAGGGUCCAUCCCUUGCAAUGUUACAUCAUCAUCAGAAAAUGUCAUAAAAUGUAUUCUUCAUUCAACUGGGAAUAUAUUCAGGAUUACCAACAAUGGGAAAGAUUCAGUACAUGGAUUAGGUUAUGCCUGGUCACCACCAGUCCUAAAUGUGUCUGUGGGGGACACAGUGGCAUGGCAUUGGCAAACACAUCCGUUUCUUAGAGGGAUAGGAUAUAGGAUUUUUUCUGUCUCCAGUCCUGGAAGUGUAAUUUAUGAUGGCAAAGGAUUCACAAGUGGAAGACAAAAAUCUACAUCAGGUUCAUUUUCUUACCAAUUUACUUCUCCUGGAAUCCAUUAUUAUAGCAGCGGGUAUGUUGAUGAGGCUCACUCCAUUUUUCUCCAAGGAGUCAUUAAUGUUUUACCAGCUGAAACCAGACACAUUCCCUUGCACCUGUUUGUGGGUCGCUCUGAAGCCACAUAUGCUUAUGGAGGACCUGAGAAUUUGCACUUGGGAAGCUCUGUGGCAGGCUGCCUAGCAACAGAACCCCUGUGCAGCCUGAACAAUACCAGGGUUAAAAAUUCAAAAAGAUUGCUAUUUGAGGUUUCAAGUUGUUUUUCACCAUCUAUAAGCAACAUUACUCCGUCCACUGGAACAGUAAAUGAACUAAUAACAAUUAUUGGACAUGGCUUUAGUAAUCUCCCAUGGGCUAAUAAGGUUACAAUUGGUAGCUACCCCUGUGUCGUAGAAGAAAGUAGUGAGGAUUCAAUUACAUGUCAUAUUGACCCUCAAAACUCAAUGGAUGUUGGUAUCAGGGAAACUGUCACUUUGACUGUCUACAACCUGGGCACUGCUAUCAAUACGUUGUCCAAUGAAUUUGAUAGGCGAUUUGUACUUUUGCCAAACAUUGACCUGGUGUUGCCAAAUGCAGGAUCAACUACAGGAAUGACAAGCGUGACCAUAAAAGGCUCUGGAUUUGCCGUUUCUUCUGCAGGUGUAAAAGUCCUUAUGGGUCAUUUCCCAUGUAAAGUUCUAUCAGUGAAUUAUACGGCCAUUGAAUGUGAAACAUCCCCUGCUGCCCAACAGCUUGUGGAUGUAGAUCUUCUAAUACAUGGAGUGCCUGCCCAGUGCCAGGGAAACUGCACCUUUUCAUACUUAGAAAGCAUCACUCCUUACAUAACAGGAGUCUUCCCAAACUCUGUCAUAGGAUCUGUAAAAGUUCUUAUUGAAGGAGAAGGUUUGGGGACUGUUUUGGAGGACAUUGCUGUUUUCAUUGGAAAUCAACAGUUCAGAGCAAUAGAGGUUAAUGAAAACAACAUCACUGCUCUUGUGACUCCUCUCCCAGUUGGACAUCAUUCUGUUAGUGUUGUGGUGGGAAGUAAAGGCUUGGCUCUGGGAAACCUGACUGUCAGCAGCCCCCCAGUAGCAUCUCUAUCACCAACUUCUGGAAGCAUUGGUGGUGGAACUACACUGGUGAUCACAGGAAAUGGCUUCUAUCCAGGCAACACUACAGUCACUAUUGGGGAUGAACCUUGUCAAAUUAUUUCCAUCAACCCCAAUGAAGUCUACUGCCGCACUCCCGCUGGGACCACUGGAAUGGUCGAUGUUAAAAUCUUUGUUAAUACAAUUGCUUAUCCACCUUUGCUUUUUACAUAUGCCCUGGAGGAUACUCCAUUUCUCAGAGGAAUUAUCCCAAGCAGAGGUCCACCAGGAACUGAAAUUGAGAUCACUGGAUCCAACUUUGGCUUUGAGAUCUUGGAAAUCUCCGUGAUGAUAAAUAACAUUCAGUGUAAUGUAACCAUGGCCAAUGAUAGUGUGGUGCAGUGCAUCGUGGGAGAUCAUGCUGGGGGCACAUUUCCUGUUAUGAUGCAUCAUAAGACAAAAGGCUCAGCCAUGUCCACAGUUGUAUUUGAGUACCCGCUUAAUAUUCAAAAUAUUAAUCCAAGCCAAGGGAGCUUUGGUGGGGGUCAAACCAUGACUGUGACAGGCACCGGAUUUAAUCCACAAAAUUCAAUUAUAUUAGUUUGUGGCUCAGAAUGUGCAAUUGACAGGCUUAGAUCUGAUUACACAACACUAUUAUGUGAAAUUCCAUCUAAUAAUGGCACGGGAGCUGAGCAAGCCUGUGAAGUGAGUGUGGUUAAUGGGAAAGAUUUGUCACAGUCCAUGACUCCGUUUACGUACGCAGUGUCACUGACUCCACUCAUCACUGCAGUAUCUCCUAAGAGAGGCAGUACAGCAGGGGGCACCAGACUGACAGUCGUGGGAUCAGGAUUCAGUGAAAAUAUGGAGGAUGUUCAUAUCACCAUAGCUGAAGCCAAAUGUGAUGUUGAGUAUUCCAACAAGACACACAUCAUCUGCAUGACAGAUGCCCAUACUCUAUCAGGGUGGGCUCCAGUUUGUGUCCACAUCAGAGGUGUCGGCAUGGCCAAACUGGAUAAUGCUGACUUUCUUUAUGUUGAUGCCUGGUCCUCCAAUUUCUCAUGGGGGGGAAAAUCUCCCCCAGAAGAAGGAUCUCUUGUUGUUAUUACAAAAGGACAGACCAUUCUGCUGGAUCAAAGCACCCCUAUUUUGAAAAUGUUGCUUAUUCAGGGUGGGACUCUAAUAUUUGAUGAAGCUGACAUUGAACUCCAGGCAGAAAAUAUUCUAAUUACAGAUGGAGGUGUUCUUCAGAUUGGAACAGAGACAUCCCCAUUCCAACACAAGGCUGUCAUUACCUUGCAUGGUCACCUGCGAUCUCCUGAGCUCCCUGUCUAUGGUGCCAAAACACUGGCUGUGCGGGAGGGAAUCCUGGAUCUGCACGGUGUGCCUGUUCCUGUGACCUGGACUCGCUUGGCUCAUACUGCAAAGGCAGGGGAAAGAAUUUUAAUUUUACAAGAAGCAGUAACAUGGAAACCAGGAGAUAACAUUGUAAUUGCAAGCACAGGACACAGACACAGUCAAGGAGAGAAUGAAAAAAUGACCAUUGCAUCUGUGUCUGCUGAUGGCAUAAACAUAACACUAAGUAACCCACUAAAUUACACACACUUAGGAAUUACGGUCACACUCCCUGAUGGAACUCUGUUUGAAGCAAGAGCAGAAGUUGGAAUUCUUACAAGAAAUAUUUUAAUAAGAGGAUCUGAUAAUGUUGAGUGGAAUAACAAAAUUCCUGCAUGUCCUGAUGGAUUUGACACAGGAGAAUUUGCUACACAGACCUGUCUCCAAGGAAAGUUUGGAGAAGAAAUAGGAAGUGACCAAUUUGGAGGCUGCGUUAUGUUUCAUGCUCCUGUACCUGGUGCUAACAUGGUAACUGGGAGAAUAGAAUAUGUAGAGGUAUUCCAUGCUGGCCAGGCUUUCCGGUUGGGGCGAUAUCCAAUACAUUGGCACCUGCUUGGAGACUUACAGUUUAAAUCUUAUGUAAGAGGCUGUGCAAUUCACCAGGCCUAUAACAGAGCUGUUACUAUUCAUAACACACACCAUCUUCUGGUUGAGAGGAAUAUUAUAUAUGAUAUUAAGGGAGGAGCAUUUUUUAUAGAAGAUGGUAUUGAACAUGGCAAUAUCCUCCAGUAUAACUUGGCAGUAUUUGUACAGCAAAGUACCAGUCUUCUGAAUGAUGAUGUGACCCCGGCUGCAUUUUGGGUCACCAACCCGAACAAUACCAUACGACACAAUGCUGUUGCUGGUGGCACUCACUUUGGCUUUUGGUACCGGAUGAACAACCACCCUGAUGGGCCAUCCUAUGACAGAAACAUUUGUCAAAAAAGAGUUCCCCUUGGCGAAUUUUUUAACAAUACUGUCCAUUCUCAAGGUUGGUUUGGAAUGUGGAUCUUUGAGGAAUAUUUCCCCAUGCAAACGGGAUCUUGUACAUCUACAGUGCCUGCACCUGCAAUAUUUAACUCACUUACUACUUGGAAUUGUCAAAAAGGAGCUGAAUGGGUCAAUGGAGGUGCCCUUCAGUUCCAUAACUUUGUGAUGGUGAAUAACUAUGAGGCUGGAAUUGAGACUAAGAGGAUCCUGGCUCCUUAUGUUGGAGGGUGGGGUGAAACCAAUGGAGCGGUGAUUAAAAAUGCCAAAAUAGUCGGCCAUCUUGAUGAACUGGGAAUGGGGUCUGCAUUUUGCACAGCAAAAGGCCUGGUUCUCCCAUUUAGUGAAGGCUUGACUGUCUCUUCUGUGCACUUUAUGAACUUUGACCGUCCCAACUGUGUAGCUUUGGGAGUGACAUCCAUCUCUGGAGUUUGUAAUGACAGAUGUGGGGGUUGGAGUGCAAAGUUUGUUGACGUCCAGUAUUCUCACACACCGAACAAGGCUGGCUUUCGCUGGGAACAUGAAAUGGUAAUGAUUGAUGUUGAUGGCUCACUUACAGGGCACAAAGGACAUACCGUCAUUCCACACAGCUCAUUGCUAGACCCUUCUCAUUGUACUCAGGAAGCUGAGUGGAGCAUUGGGUUCCCUGGAUCAGUCUGUGAUGCUUCAGUCAGCUUUCACCGUUUAGCGUUCAACCAGCCUUCUCCAGUAUCUCUGCUUGAAAAGGAUGUGGUUCUUUCAGACUCUUUUGGCACAAGCAUUAUUCCAUUUCAGAAGAAACGACUGACUCAUAUGUCUGGAUGGAUGGCUCUGAUUCCAAAUGCAAAUCACAUUAACUGGUAUUUUAAAGGUGUGGAUCACAUAACCAACAUUUCAUAUACAUCGACAUUCUAUGGAUUCAAGGAAGAAGACUAUGUAAUUAUAUCACAUAACUUCACUCAAAAUCCUGACAUGUUUAAUAUUAUUGAUAUGAGGAAUGGUUCCUCAAAUCCAUUGAAUUGGAAUACUAGCAAGAAUGGGGACUGGCACCUUGAAGCAAACACUAGUACUCUAUAUUACUUGGUGUCAGGAAGAAAUGACCUUCAUCAGAGUCAGCUCAUUUCUGGGAACCUGGAUCCUGAUGUGAAAGACGUUGUUAUUAAUUUCCAAGCUUACUGUUGUAUUCUCCAGGAUUGCUUUCCUGUACAUCCGCCAUCAAGAAAACCAAUUCCCAAGAAGCGACCAGCCACAUAUAAUUUAUGGUCAAAUGAUUCUUUUUGGCAAUCAUCACGAGAAAAUAAUUAUACUGUACCUCACCCAGGGGCAAAUGUGAUUAUACCUGAAGGAACAUGGAUUGUAGCUGACAUAGAUAUGCCAUCAAUGGAAAGACUCAUUAUUUGGGGGGUUCUAGAACUGGAAGAUAAAUACAAUGUAGGAGCUGCAGAAUCUUCUUACAGAGAAGUUGUUUUGAAUGCUACCUACAUAUCACUGCAGGGAGGUAGAUUAAUCGGUGGCUGGGAAGAUAACCCUUUUAAAGGAGACUUAAAGAUUGUUCUUAGAGGAAAUCAUACUACACAAGACUGGGCUCUUCCAGAAGGACCAAAUCAAGGGGCAAAGGUCUUAGGGGUGUUUGGUGAGCUGGAUCUUCAUGGAAUUCCACAUUCAAUAUAUAAAACUAAGCUCUCAGAAACUGCAUUUGCAGGUUCCAAAGUCCUGUCUCUGAUGGAUGCUGUGGAUUGGCAGGAGGGAGAAGAGAUUGUGAUAACAACCACAAGCUACGAUUUCCACCAGACAGAAACAAGAAGUAUCGUUAAAAUCCUGCAUGAUCAUAAAAUUCUCAUUCUUAAUGAUAGCCUUUCCUAUACUCACUUUGCUGAAAAAUACCAUGUCCCUGGAACUGGUGAGAGCUACACGUUAGCAGCUGAUGUUGGGAUACUGAGUAGGAACAUCAAAAUAGUUGGUGAAGAUUACCCCGGUUGGUCUGAGGACUCUUUUGGAGCACGCGUACUGGUUGGCUCAUUCACUGAAAAUAUGAUGACAUUUAAAGGAAAUGCAAGAAUAAGUAAUGUGGAAUUUUAUCACAGUGGUCAAGAAGGCUUCAGGGAUAGCACAGAUCCAAGAUAUGCUGUAACGUUUCUUAACCUAGGACAGAUUCAAGAACAUGGCUCAUCUUAUAUUCGAGGCUGUGCUUUUCACCAUGGCUUCUCUCCAGCAAUUGGUGUAUUUGGGACAGAUGGAUUGGACAUAGAUGACAACAUCAUUCACUUUACAGUGGGGGAAGGCAUAAGAAUAUGGGGGAAUGCCAACCGAGUCCGAGGGAAUUUGAUUGCACUUUCGGUUUGGCCAGGAACCUAUCAGAACAGAAAAGAUUUAAGUUCAACUCUCUGGCAUGCAGCAAUUGAGAUAAAUAGAGGGACCAAUACAGUUUUACAGAAUAAUGUAGUGGCUGGAUUUGGAAGAGCAGGAUACCGCAUUGAUGGUGAACCUUGCCCAGGCCAGUUUAAUCCUGUGGAAAAGUGGUUUGACAAUGAAGCCCAUGGAGGUUUAUAUGGGAUCUAUAUGAACCAAGAUGGCCUUCCUGGAUGUUCUCUUAUACAAGGAUUUACCAUUUGGACAUGCUGGGAUUAUGGAAUUUAUUUUCAGACCACAGAGAGUGUGCACAUUUAUAAUGUGACCCUGGUUGACAAUGGAAUGGCCAUUUUUCCAAUGAUUUACAUGCCAGCUGCUAUAUCACACAAAAUUUCCAGUAAAAAUGUACAAAUUAAGAGCUCAUUAAUUGUUGGAAGUAGCCCUGGGUUUAAUUGCUCUGAUGUCCUAACUAAUGAUGAUCCUAAUAUUGAACUCACUGCUGCUCAUCGGAGUCCUAGAUCUCCAUCAGGUGGGAGAAGUGGGAUUUGUUGGCCUACCUUUGCUUCAGCUCAUAACAUGGCACCCCGAAAGCCCCAUGCAGGAAUCAUGAGUUACAAUGCCAUCAGUGGCCUUUUGGACAUCUCAGGUUCAACAUUUGUUGGAUUUAAGAAUGUUUGUUCAGGGGAAACUAAUGUUAUAUUCAUUACUAACCCUUUAAAUGAGGAUUUACAGCAUCCAAUCCAUGUGAAGAAUAUAAAACUGGUUGAUACCACUGAACAAUCAAAAAUAUUUAUACAUAGGCCUGAUAUAAGUAAGGUCAAUCCAUCUGAUUGUGUAGACAUGGUUUGUGAUGCCAAGAGGAAAUCUUUUCUUAGAGACAUAGAUGGCUCCUUUCUGGGGAAUGCUGGUUCUGUGAUACCUCAAGCAGAAUAUGAAUGGGACGGAAACAGCCAAGUAGGAAUUGGAGACUACAGAAUUCCUAAGGCGAUGCUCACAUUCUUGAAUGGAAGUAGAAUUCCUGUCACUGAGAAAGCACCUCAUAAAGGAAUUAUUAGAGAUUCAACCUGUAAGUACCUUCCAGAGUGGCAGAGCUAUCAGUGCUUUGGGAUGGAAUAUGCAAUGAUGGUUAUUGAAAGUCUGGAUCCUGACACAGAAACUCGAAGACUUUCCCCAGUGGCUAUAAUGGGCAACGGUUAUGUUGAUCUUAUUAAUGGCCCACAGGAUCAUGGCUGGUGUGCUGGAUAUACAUGCCAGAGAAGGCUGUCCCUGUUUCACAGCAUUGUGGCUCUGAACAAAUCUUAUGAAGUUUACUUCACUGGCACCAGUCCUCAGAAUCUUCGACUGAUGUUGCUUAAUGUUGAUCAUAACAAGGCUGUUCUAGUAGGAAUUUUCUUUUCCACACUUCAACGUUUGGAUGUCUAUGUGAACAACUUAUUGGUCUGUCCAAAAACUACAAUAUGGAAUGCCCAGCAGAAACACUGUGAACUUAAUAACCAUCUGUACAAAGACCAAUUCCUUCCUAACCUGGAUUCCACUGUCCUUGGUGAAAACUACUUUGAUGGAACCUACCAGAUGCUUUAUCUUUUGGUUAAAGGAACUAUACCUGUUGAAAUUCACACUGCCACAGUGAUAUUUGUUUCUUUCCAAUUAUCUGUUGCAACAGAAGAUGACUUUUAUACCUCUCACAAUCUGGUUAAAAAUCUUGCCUUGUUCCUAAAGAUACCAAGUGACAAAAUCCGUAUCAGCAAAAUAAGAGGGAAGAGUCUGAGGAGGAAGAGAUCCAUGGGAUUCAUAAUUGAAAUAGAGAUUGGAGACCCUCCUAUUCAGUUCAUAAGCAAUGGCACCACAGGUCAGAUGCAGUUAUCUGAACUCCAGGAAAUUGCUGGUUCUCUUGGACAAGCUGUAAUUUUAGGAAACAUCAGUAGUAUCCUUGGAUUUAACAUUUCGUCCAUGUCUAUUACUAAUCCCCUCCCCAGCCCAAGUGACUCUGGGUGGAUUAAGGUGACUGCCCAGCCAGUUGAAAGGUCUGCAUUUCCUGUUCAUCACGUGGCCUUCGUGUCCUCACUCUUAGUGAUCACUCAGCCGGUGGCAGCACAGCCAGGACAGCCAUUUCCUCAGCAGCCUUCGGUAAAGGCAACAGAUUCUGACGGUAACUGUGUAUCAGUUGGAAUUACUGCACUAACUUUGAGGGCCAUACUCAAGGACUCCAAUAAUAACCAAGUCAAUGGCCUUAGUGGAAAUACAACAAUUCCGUUUAGCAGCUGUUGGGCCAACUACACAGACCUUACUCCCCUUAGAACAGGAAAAAAUUAUAAGAUUGAAUUUAUACUGGAUAAUGUUGUUGGGGUAGAAUCCAGAACUUUCAGCCUGCUGGCAGAGUCUGUCUCUAGCAGUGGCAGCAGCAGCAGCAGCAACAGCAAAGCAUCAACUGUGGGUACAUAUGCCCAGAUAAUGACUGUAGUAAUUAGCUGUCUGGUUGGAAGAAUGUGGCUCUUGGAAAUAUUUAUGGCUGCAGUUUCAACUUUGAAUAUAACUUUAAGAAGCUACUAAAGUGCUGUUCCGAAGAAUAGGCUGAAACAAAAAUAUAAGAAUUAUUAGCUACUUUGUUGGGCAAUAGGCAAAAGUCUAUAGCAUUUUCAUGAAAAUAUACUAAAAAUAUUUUUAUGAUAUAUAAAAUGUACUAAUUAGCUUUAAACACUAAAAUCAGAUUUCUUCAAAAUAUAAAUUUGUUUUGAUUCUUUAUAUUUAUAUGUUUUUAUUUCAUUUCAAUAAACUUCCAGAAAUUUGUCAUUUGGAAGUAGAUAUGACACCUCUAAGUUAUUGUACCAACAAAUCAUAGAAUCCUUUAAAUAAUGGAAAGAGCUUGUCUAGUUCCGACUUAAGCUCUUUACAUCAGAUUGGAAGCAUUUUAAGUAUUCUUUUUAAUACUUGAGGGGGGGGGUUCUUAUUUUCUCUAUCCAUUUACAAGGUUUUGAUUUCCAAUAAUCUAAGCCAUUCUAGUUUCUAAGGAUUUUGGAGAGACGAGAUUGUCUUCACACAAUCUGAGAUGACAAUCUCAUCUCAGAUUUUUCACACUGAGUUCCUGUCUUUCAGAUUCACAGUAAUCCCAGGAAUUCUAGACUGUCCUGUAUUUCUGGAUCUGCCCAACUCUGGCCAAUAUUGGGAAAAGUUUUCUUGUCCUUGGAAUGAACUUUUGGAACAAGUCCAAACUCCUUCUCUGCCUACCCCUCCUUCCCACUCAAAACUGCCACUACUAAGAGCAGGACUCCCCUCAACCCCGGGCAUGAGUUGAGGGUUGAGGGGUUCCCUUAACUGGUGGAUGCUUAUUCACUGUUUACUGGAUGAAUGAAGUAUAAAGUGUGGGAAGUCAACAACAGAACAGAACUUAUUUUCAAGAAGAUAAAUUAGAGAAUGCAAAAAAGCUACAGACUAAGGUAGCUAAGUUAACCGAACUCUCUAACAGUAUUGAAAAUAGCAAUUCUUUACUCAGAAAAUUCUAAAGGGAAUACUUAAUUUGACAGAACUCCUAAUAAAGACAUUGUAGCCAGAUCCAGAGCCUUCCAGCAAGUGACACUCAGCAAACAUUUGGGACAGCUGAGAGAAUUCAACAAAGCCCAUACCGUUGUCUCUUGUAUAACAUCUCCUAGUACAUUCACCUCAGAUCAUUGUUAGUCUUACUUAGCAGAAAAUGUAUAAACACUUACCAGGUAGUAAAAUCAAAUAUCUUGGUAUAAAUGUGGCAUUUCAUUCACUUGAGCAGUAUCUGUUGGGUGUUCUAGUAAGUAGGAAGGCUACAAGAAAUAAGAUGCUAUGCCUUCCCUCGAAGAGUUUUCAGGAUAUUUGGGGAAAGAAUGGAAACAGACCAUUUCAAUACAACAUGAUCACUGUCUCAGGGAGAGAGAGACAGAGAAAGACAGAGAGAUAGAGACAGAGACAGAGAGGGAGGGGGAGAGAGAGAUAGAUAGAGAGAGAGAGAAAGCAUGAGGUUGCUAGCAAUAUGGAGGCCUUAAGCCUUGUUCAGGAGGGCUACCUAGAAGAGCAGUGGAAGAAAACUGGGAGAGGACCACUGAAGGCCUAGGGGCUACAGAAAAAAUUCAAAUGAACAGCUGGAAUGGAAAUAGUCACAAUUUUAAGGGAAUUGCAGGUAAGAGGUCCCUGACAAGGUAGUCUUCAAAGUAUACAUGAAAGCCCCUUCAUGAGGAACAUUUGCCAUGUCCAGAGAGCAUUGAUACUUCAUUGUACAGCACCAGGUAACAGAGCACUUUUAUACUCCCCUCAGUUCCAACCCUGGUGGGGUGAAAAACCUCUGUUCCUGGGAUAGGGAGGGGGAAAGAGACCCAACAUGGGCCAUUUCACGCUGAGACUUAAAAAUCAGUCUUCCUAAGGCAAAUCUAGUUUACUGUUCAUUCCGUGAUACUUCCUUUCUGUUGGAAAACUAAAUUCCAAAAACUGCAAUUCCAGCAUCUAUGGAACAAAUUCCUACAUUUGGGUUCUGGAAGAGAUACAAAAAUAUUCUUCACACCAGAACAUUGUAAAAGCCAUAAAAUUGUCCACCAUCUGUAUUCUUUUCUUACCUAAAGGUUUAAUUCAGCCCACUGGAGUUUUUUGUCAAGAUUUUUUCUGUCAGUUUUUAAUAAGGAAAUUUUCUAAUACAAGUUAUAUGGCAGUAAAAGGAAUUUCUAAAAAUUGCUUCUUAGCCACACAGACUUUGUUAAAAAGUUCCUGUUUUAACUGCUUUAGGCUUCUGGCUGUCUGCUUUUUAAGAACAUUCUAGAAUUAUCAUAAUAAUUCCUUAUUCCAGAUAAAUUACAAUUUAAUUACUACUUUUAAAAAUGCUUGAAUUAUUGGAAUCCAUGGGCAAUACAUCUUCACAUGUCCCUUAUUCAUAUGCUAAGCAAGUUUUAUUUUUGCUUUUUUUUUGCAUUUAAAUAAUAUUUCUCUGAACAUUCUGUCUCAGAAAUUGAUGUUUAAAUUCUUAAAAAUAAUUUGUAUUGUAAGAAGUGGCUAUCUAGCUCUUGAACAAGUCAUAAAAAUCCUUUGAUGUGUGAAUAUUCUUCUACCUAAGACCUGAAAUGUUGGCGAAGUAAAUAUGUUGUUCCAAUUUUGGUCAAAGUAAGAAACAGAGAAUAAAAAGUUAAUAAGAAUAGCUUCUUGUAUUUCUCAUAGUAAGUGAAAUGUUUAUAUCUUGUACUACUGUCUCUACUCAUUCCUAAAUUCCAUCACCUUGUGAUCAUUGCAAUGACUUCUAGAUGGUCCAUCUGUUUUUACCUUUUAUCCAUUUUAUCCCCAAAAGUGCUAUUUAAAAUAUCCCUAGCACUAAUAAUAACAAUAAUCAAUAAUAAAGUAAAGGUUUAUCACAUGUUCACUACAUGCCAGACACUAUGCUGUGUGUUCUACAUGGACCCUUUCCUUACAGCAAUCCUAUGAGGAUAACCUUAUUCCCUUCUCCAAAUGAGGAAACUUGAAAUGUUGAAGGGUUAGGUUAAAUUCCCAAGUUCACAGAGCUACUAAUGGUAAAGCUGGGAUUCAAACACAGACAAUUUAACUCCAGAGCCCAAAUUCCAACAUUUAAUUGCUUCCCACUUUUCCUCAAGCAUGGGCAAGUGCUUCAUUGGGAAGAGUUUUUAAUCCAAAUUCCUGUUCAAAUUCUUGGUUUCUACUUUACCACUUCUAUGCCCUCAGGCAAGUUCUUAGUUUCCAUUAUUCUCAGUUUCUUCAACUGUAAAAUGUGGAAAGUGUGACAUCUGAAGACUGAUGGUAUCAUAUAUAUGACAUGUAACACAGUGCCUAACAGGCGGUAAAAUGAUAGCCACUCUUGUUUUUAUUUCCAUAAUGUGGCCUAUAUCAUGUCAAUCCCUGGCCCAGUAAACCAUUAGGCUUCUUAUUACACUGGAACAGUGCCUGGCAUGUAAUAAGCACCAUGUGAGUGCUAAUUAUUAGAAUUAUUGGCUGGGCACUGGGCCACCUAGAACAAAGACAAUUUCCCAGCUUCACUUGCAGUGAGACUGAUCAAUUUCUGUGCAGUGGGUUACAAAAACAGACAUUAUCUCGUGGCAUAUUCUAGAAACUGACCUUAAAACAUAGCUAUUAUGCAUCCCUUUGCCUUUUCUUCAUCCCUUUCUGUUUUUCCAGCUACAUGGAGCAAGAUGGCUCCUGAGACCUGGAGGAUAAAGGCCAGUGCCUUUUAUUGCUCCAUAACUUGUGUUAGAAAAUCUCCUUACUAAAAAUCUACAGAAAAAUCUUGACAAAAAAAAAAUUCCAGUGGAUUGAAUUAAAACUUUAGGUAAGAAAAGACUAAGAUGGUGGACAAUUUUAUGGCUUUUACAAUGUCCUUGUGUGAAGAAUAUUUUUAUACCUCUUCCAGAACCCAGAGAGCUCAGCUGAAAGGAGUUUGGGUUCCUGACAUUGUGGUGCCCUAUACCAGCCCUUGCUCCUUUAGGGUUUCAUUGUUAUUUGGUGGUUAUCCUAAAUCUCCUGCUUUCAUCAGAUGUCUGAGAUGGCAAAAUUUGGAAGGAUCAAGAGAACAGAGAGUUAAUCCUUCCUAAUGGGAAAGGUGGACAAUGCCAAGGUUAAAAUACCACAUGCAUCUUUGAGUUACUACUAUACCCUCCCGAAUGGAAAUGCUUCAACUUUAAUCUGAGGCUAGGCGCAGUGGCUCACGCCUGUAAUCCCAGCACUCUGGGAGGCCAAGGCAGGCGGAUCACGAGGUCAGGAGAUCGAGACUAUCCUGGCUAACACAGUGAAAUCCUGUCUCUACUAAAAAUACAAAAAAAUUAGCCAGGCAUGGUGGCGGGCACCUGUAGUCUCAGCUAGUCGGGAGGCUGAGGCAGGAGAAUGGUGUGAACCCAGGAGGCGGAGCUUGCAGUGAGCUGAGAUCUCGCCACUGCACUCCAGCCUGGGUGACAGAGCGAGACACAUCUCAAAAAAAAAAACCCAAAAAACUUUAAUCUGAAUCCAUUAUGUGUUGGGUUGGGUUGGGGAACCUACCAAAACAGUGGGAGAGUCUUGCCCUUUUUCUAAGAUCAUCAGUGGGCAUUUUCAGCUUCCCCAUUAUGGUAGUAGCUGCAAGGAGUGUUCAGUCUCCAGUGAAAGAAAUAUUAAGAUUUAUUCCCCCAAUUUCCCCUCCCCAGAGAGUAGCUACAGACACACUGUGUAAGACCAAAUAGGAAAAGUCUGCCACAGGGGACACAGUAGGUACUUGAAUACUUGUGGGCAGUCUAACCAGCUACAAACCUCUUGUUGCCGUACUUGCAAGUCCUAAUACAGUACUGUAGUUAUUAUAAUUCCAUCAUUCUGAAAUUAGAAAGAUGGUCAUGGAGAAACUGUUCUAAGAACGCCAUUCACCCAUGAAUGUGACUUUAUUAGAGGUUUUUUUUUUAGGUUAAGGACUAUGUAUUCUUUCAAUUUCUCUAAAGUGCUUAGCACACACUCUGCCCAUGGUAAGUGUUAAAUAAACUUUCUGAUAAACCAAUGAUUGGGUAGCAUGAUGAAACUUUUCCUAUCCUGCUUUUUGAGAUUAAGAAAUCUUUUAAAAAUAUUACAGAAACUGCACUUUAUCCUGACUUACAGCCUUAAUGUUUGAAGUAGCAGUGUAUAAAAUUCACACCCAGUUAUAGACUGAGUAAUUAUAGUUGCUAUGGUAAUGGGCUCUGUGCCUAUGAGCAAAAAAAAAAAAUUCCUUUUGUGCAAGAUAUUUAUGACUGUGCCUGGCUACAUGGCAAUAGUAUUUUCCUUUGGUUUUUCAUUACAGUAACUUAUGCAUUUAGGCAGAUGAUCCUUUAUAUAUGUAAACGCUAUAAAUUCUUAGGAAGAAAAUAAAUUUAUUAAGUUUUUCACAUCAAAAAUUUCUAGUAUGAUUAUGAGUUCAAUUUUCAAGUGAAAGUAAUCCUUAAAGGAUUUAAUUUCAAAUAAGAACUACGUACAAAAUAUAGAUUUAAAUUAAUUUUCACUGUAUGAAAUGUACAGUAUACAUAGACCAACUCCUUUAACAAGAAUUUCUGGUAUGUCUUAAAGGGCAUGGGUGGUUAGAGGGAGAUCCCCAAACAAACAAUUCAAAAUUAAGAGUUUAAAAAGCAACAAUCAAGACACAUAUCCUCCUAAGUGAAUUUGAAUUAGACACUGGAAAAUUUAAAAAGGUCAGUUACUAUGAAGAAGGUGUAACAAUAUUUAUAUUAAUCAGACAGCAAAGUAACAAACUGACUUAGAGGAAGGAAAAUAGUAAAAUACAAAAGACUAAGUUAGCAGAUCAUUUUGAUAUCCAGAUGUGCUGAAAUGAUGGACACUGAGAAGAAAGAAUAGACAAAACUUGGCAACAGAUCUUGGUAUGAAAUAAAUAUCCCAUGAGUAGUACAUAAAAGCCUGGAGAGAGAGGGGAAGGAUUGUAAGUGUCAUAGUUCUGACAGCUGCUCUUUCAUCCUAUGCCUUUAAAACAAAGGGAACAAAGAAGGGAACAAAGAAGGUAGAAGCGGGGGUAUGGAGGGUUGACUUCUGGCUGUCCCUCCCUGUUUCCCUUUGUUAAUAUAUUGCUAGUAGACAUGUCUACUUCUGGUUGCUGAUGACAUAAAAUUCACCUCUAUUUCUUGGAAGCACUAUUCCAUGUUGUGAGCUAAAGGGGAUUGUACUGAUCUUGAAGAUAACAAAUCUGCCUGCUUCAAAGGUUUCACCGAUUUUAUUGCUGUGUUUCCAACACAUUUCCACAUAUGGUAUGAUAUUUAAUUUGCAAAAUAAAUCCGUAAAGCAGGAAUUACUAACCUAAUUUUGCAGAUGAGAAAACUGAGGCUUAAAGUUGUUCAAGGUCAAAGUCACGAUGUCCAUCAUGCUGUAGCUCAAUGAAUGAGUCUCACAUUGUUUCAUGUUGUUUUAUUUCUACUUUCUCAAUCCAUGUACAAGAUAGAUUUACAAACUACUGUUUUAUGUUGGUUGUAUGAAUUUCAAUACAUUUACUGUUAGAAAUAACAAAAGGUCUUAGACUGCCAGAUGCUGUUCCCAUCAACUCUACUUAAUUCAUAAUAUAGCUGAACUCUGUCAUAAAUCUAAUAACGAUGUGGACAUUAGCCAGAAGUAUGAUGUGGCUGAACCUCACCACUGAACACAAAAUGAGAAUUCACCUCAUCUUUUCAUUUGAAUUUAUUUCUACUAAAAUAUAUGUAUUAUUUUUCUUGAUUUCUAACCAGGCCCCUUCUGAAGAAAACUGGUUAACUCUAAAUUGUUACUAAAUUUUGAAUCUUCCUGUAUUUAGCAAUAAAAGUUACUGCUAAUUGUAAUAACAAUUAUGAGGAAAAAUUUAUUUAAAUGCUUCAUAGAAAGUUAAUUUUCAUUUAAUAGAAAAGAAAUAAAAAAUCUGCUUCAGACUGUUUGAUUUCUCUAUUAGGCAAUUGACCCUAACUAGUAUAUGGUGAUUUUGAGUAUUAAAAAAGAAGUUAUAAUUUUCCAGAAUAUUAAUGUUUAUUAUUUUGAAAGCAAGUAAAAUUCUCCAGUAGGAAGAUUAAUAAAACAAUUCAUUAAAAUUCUCAUCAGAAAAUCCUAUGCUUUCAAAUGUAUCUGCUCAAAGAUGUCACUCUAUGUGCGGCAAAGCUUUGUUUUACUUGAUCAAGAAAUGAAUGUGACUUUAUGAUCUUGUAUUCAACUGUGAACAGCUGCUCAUUAAUAAAAAGCCAUUAAAGUCCAA